CUAGCACAUGCAGAUGACAAUCCAGGCUCUCCAGGAUGAAUUGCGGAUCCAGAGGGACCUGAAUCAGCUGUUUCAGCAGGAUAGUAGCAGCAGGACUGGCGAACCUUGUGUAGCAGAGCUGACAGAGGAGAACUUUCAGAGGCUUCAUGCUGAGCAUGAGCGGCAGGCCAAAGAGCUGUUUCUUCUUCGAAAGACAUUGGAGGAAAUGGAGCUGCGUAUUGAGACUCAAAAGCAGACCCUAAAUGCUCGGGAUGAAUCCAUUAAGAAGCUUCUGGAAAUGUUGCAGAGCAAAGGACUUUCUGCCAAGGCUACCGAGGAAGACCAUGAGAGAACAAGACGACUGGCAGAGGCAGAGAUGCACGUUCAUCACCUAGAAAGCCUUUUGGAGCAGAAGGAAAAAGAGAACAGUAUGUUGAGAGAGGAGAUGCAUCGAAGGUUUGAGAAUGCUCCUGAUUCUGCCAAAACAAAAGCUCUGCAAACUGUUAUUGAGAUGAAGGAUUCAAAAAUUUCCUCUAUGGAGCGUGGGCUUCGAGACCUGGAAGAGGAAAUUCAGAUGCUGAAAUCGAAUGGUGCUUUGAGUACUGAGGAAAGGGAAGAAGAAAUGAAGCAAAUGGAAGUGUAUCGGAGCCAUUCUAAAUUUAUGAAAAAUAAGGUAGAACAACUGAAGGAGGAACUAAGUUCGAAAGAGGCUCAAUGGGAGGAGCUGAAAAAGAAAGCGGCUGGUCUUCAGGCUGAGAUUGGCCAGGUGAAACAGGAGCUGUCCAGAAAGGACACAGAACUACUCGCCCUGCAGACAAAGCUAGAAACACUCACAAACCAGUUCUCAGAUAGUAAACAGCACAUUGAAGUGUUGAAGGAGUCCUUGACUGCUAAGGAGCAGAGGGCUGCCAUCCUGCAGACUGAGGUAUUAAGGGCCGUGGCUCACGCCUGUAAUCCCAGCCCUUUGGGAGGCUGAAGCGGGCGGAUCAUGAGGUCAAGAGAUCGACACCAUUCUGGCCAACAUGGUGAAACCCCGUCUCUACUAAAAAUAAAAAAAUUAGCUGGGCGUGGUGGCACGUGCCUGUAGUCCCAGCUACUCAGGAGGCUGAGGCAGGAGAAUUGCUUGAACCCAGGAGGCGGAGGUUGCAGUGAGCUGAGAUCAUGCCACUGCACUCCAGCCUGGCGACAGAGUGAGAUUCUGUCUCAAAAAAAAAAAAAAAAAAAAAAA